GGAUACACUGUUGCUGAGUCUAGACACCAGAAGAACGUUGCAGGCGGCGACUCACAGUUCUAGCACUGCCUAGGAGAGCGUGGUGGCCCCAGCUCAGAAUCUGCAGAAGUGCACAGCUCCAUCCACACCACUCAGGGUAUGGAGCCUCCGGACCAGUGUAGCCAGUAUAUGACCAGCUUGCUCAGCCCUGCAGUCGACGACGAGAAAGAACUACAGGAUAUGAAUGCUAUGGUGCUGUCGCUUACUGAAGAGGUCAAAGAGGAGGAAGAGGAUGCACAGCCUGAGCCUGAGCAAGGCACAGCAGCAGGAGAAAAGUUAAAGUCGGCAGGAGCCCAAGGCGGAGAAGAAAAAGAUGGCGGCGGAGAAGAAAAAGAUGGCGGCGGCGCCGGAGUUCCUGGCCACCUAUGGGAAGGAGACCUCGAGGGCACCAGCGGCAGCGAUGGCAACGUUGAGGACAGCGACCAGAGCGAGAAGGAACCUGGGCAGCAGUAUUCGCGCCCACAGGGCGCCGUCGGGGGGCUGGAGCCUGGCAACGCGCAGCAGCCCAACGUCCACGCCUUCACCCCAUUGCAGCUGCAGGAGCUGGAGCGCAUUUUCCAACGCGAGCAGUUCCCCAGUGAGUUCCUGCGAAGGAGGCUGGCAAGAAGCAUGAAUGUGACUGAACUCGCAGUGCAGAUUUGGUUUGAGAAUAGAAGAGCCAAAUGGAGGAGACAUCAGAGGGCAUUAAUGGCAAGAAACAUGCUGCCCUUCAUGGCAGUGGGCCAGCCUGUCAUGGUAACCGCAGCUGAGGCCAUAACGGCACCCUUGUUCAUCAGCGGGAUGAGAGAUGAUUACUUCUGGGACCACAGCCAUUCCAGCAGCCUGUGUUUCCCCAUGCCACCCUUUCCUCCUCCGUCCUUGCCCCUUCCACUCAUGCUUCUUCCACCUAUGCCACCCGCUGGCCAGGCUGAAUUUGGCCCAUUCCCUUUUGUUAUCGUGCCUUCUUUCACAUUCCCCAAUGUCUAAGGGAUAGCCUCUGUGCCACUUUUUGCCAGAGUGUCUUUGAGCCAGAUUCAUAUUUUGCAUAGCACCCCAUCAAAAGUAGUUCAUCAAAUGUCUAUUAAACGUUUUAAAGAAAAGUACAUCAUUGACCCAUUUUUAGGGCACUUGUAAAAAUGUUUCUAUAAAUAUGUGAAGGGUAUGUACAUUUGUUUUGUGUGUCACAUGGGGUCAGUAAGUUCUCAAUAAAAAUUGUUAAGAAAUGCCAUUCAAACCGAAUGUCACGGACUCUCGUCUCAUGCAGUAAUCUUGAGUCACCAUCUGGGGGCUGUGCAUGUCACAGAAUUUUCCCAUGUGCCCAUGGCAGGCUUACACCGACCCAGACAUUCUCUUCCACCCCCACCCCCAACACCCCAUACUCAUCUCCUCUCUGCCCCCAUUGAUACCAGGUACAUGUGCAGGAUGGGGUGGUGUGAGUCCCUAAUGAGAGAAUAGUGUGUUUCAAGUUACUGCCAGGGUGGAAAACAGCAAAACCAAAAUGGUAUCGGGAAGGAAGCCAUGCCCACUCUUAAAAAUUCAUUAAGUUUUUUCUUGCUAUGGAAGACUUCUUUAAAGUAAUUUUCUUGUAAAAGUGUAAGUGUAAAUAAUGCCAUGAAAUUAUACACUUAUUUAAUGGCUAAAAUGGCAAAUUUUUAUAUGGUUUACCACAACAAAAGAAAAGAAAAAAUAUACCAAAAAGUUUUUAAAAAGUGAUCAUGAACAUUGUGGUCAUCCUGUGAAGUGAUUGCAAUGCCUGCAGAUAAGGAGUGAUGGUUACAACAGUAUUUUCUCUGAAAAUUAUUUGAUGGCCAGUUUCAUAAUGAUUAUGUUUUCAGCCUGAAGGAAAAUUCCAUUUUCUUGGGUGAGCAUGAACUUUCUGUCAGGCUGUCUGCUGCUUUUCAUUCCCCACUUCUCUCUUCACAAUUGUGGGUGUCAAGCUUCAGCCACGCAAUUGCAUUUGGUGUGAGGGUUUUGCAAGGAGAAGGAGGUUUAUUCAUACCCCUGAAGCCACAAGCCUUGGUGGGAAUAAGGAAAGUCCAUGAAUUCACUAUGCAUUAAUGCAUGCCUCUUGGCCAAGUGGAUUCUUUUUUCUUCUCCGAUUGAGAUUUUCCUUUUUUUUUUUUUUUUUUUUUUUUGCUCUUGUUCUCAUUGUAUUGUGCUUUGUAUAAUUAUUUACAGUAAGUCGCGCAUGUCAGUGUACAUUCCGUCUGGAAAUUGUUUCCAUUUGGUACAUUUUGUGCCAGUCGGUCUAUUCCUGCUCAUUAUUUUGUUUUUUCUACAUUCAGACUGAAACAUUUGGUAGCCUAGAGAUACUCAGAAAUAGGCAAAGAAAGGUAAAAGGGGAGGAGGGGAGAUUGAAAUCAUACUUCCAUUAUCCCUCCCCGUGGUUAUCAGAUUCAUAAAAUUUUUACACCAUCAAAAGACAUUUUUAGCCAUAUAUGUUUCCUUUAUGUAGAAAAUGAGAUCUCCUAUACUCAGUUGGCAUUUGUUUUCAUGUAUCUGAUAAGUACCUGUUAGAAUUAUAGGUCAAGAUGUUGUCUAGCUCUGGUAACCUAGAUCCUGAACUUCAAAGCAGAGUUCUUGGACCUUAAGAAAUUCAAAUUCGUAGAAUUAUAGUUAGGAUGUCAUUUACUGACCUUGAACAACACAUUGUUUAGGUAGCAUACAAUGGGACUAGUUCAAGGGGCUGGGUGGAGAACAAGUUACAAUUUUUUCUGAUGGAGAACAUUACUGGAGACAGUACCCUUUAAAACUUUCAUUCCCUUUUUAUUAGCAGCUAACGUCUUGUAUGCCUUUACUAUGUGACAAGCAAUAAAAUAAUGUCCUUGGA